GCAAUGGCGGUUCCCGGCGUGGGGCUCUUGACCCGUUUGAACCUGUGUGCCCGGAGAAGAACUCGAGUCCAGCGGCCUAUCGUCAGGCUUUUGAGUUGCCCAGGAACUGUGGCCAAAGACCUUAGGAGAGACGAGCAGCCUUCAGGGAGCGUGGAGACAGGCUUUGAAGACAAGAUUCCCAAAAGGAGAUUCUCUGAGAUGCAAAAUGAAAGACGAGAACAGGCACAGCGGACUGUUUUAAUACAUUGCCCAGAGAAAAUCAGUGAAAACAAGUUUCUUAAAUAUUUAUCCCAAUUUGGACCUAUUAAUAAUCAUUUCUUCUAUGAAAGCUUUGGUCUCUAUGCUGUCGUAGAAUUUUGCCAAAAGGAAAGCAUAGGUUCACUGCAGAAUGGGACUCAUACUCCAAGCACGGCCAUGGAGACUGCAAUUCCAUUCAGAUCACGUUUCUUCAAUCUGAAGUUGAAAAACCAGACUUCUGAACGGUCACGCGUACGGUCAAGUAAUCAGUUGCCACGUUCAAACAAGCAGCUUUUUGAAUUACUUUGUUAUGCAGAAAGUAUAGACGAUCAGCUGAACACUCUCUUGAAGGAGUUCCAGCUAACAGAGGAGAACACUAAGCUCCGAUAUCUCACCUGUUCUCUUAUUGAAGACAUGGCCGCCGCGUAUUUUCCAGACUGCAUAGUCAGACCCUUUGGCUCCUCAGUCAACACUUUUGGGAAGUUAGGAUGUGAUUUGGACAUGUUUUUGGAUCUAGAUGAAACCAGAAACCUCAGCGCUCACAAGAUCUCAGGAAAUUUUCUGAUGGAAUUUCAAGUGAAAAAUGUUCCUUCAGAAAGAAUUGCAACUCAGAAGAUCCUGUCUGUGUUAGGAGAGUGCCUUGACCACUUUGGCCCUGGCUGUGUGGGUGUGCAAAAAAUAUUAAAUGCCCGGUGUCCGCUCGUGAGGUUCUCACACCAGGCCUCCGGAUUUCAGUGUGAUUUGACUACGAACAAUAGGAUUGCCUUGACAAGUUCCGAACUCCUUUAUAUAUAUGGUGCCCUAGACUCAAGAGUGAGAGCCUUGGUGUUCAGUGUACGGUGCUGGGCUCGAGCACAUUCACUAACAAGUAGUAUUCCUGGUGCAUGGAUUACAAAUUUCUCCCUUACAAUGAUGGUCAUCUUUUUUCUCCAGAGAAGAUCACCCCCUAUUCUUCCAACACUAGAUUCCUUAAAAACCCUAGCAGAUGCAGAAGAUAAAUGUGUAAUAGAAGGCAACAACUGCACAUUUGUUCGUGACUUGAGUAGAAUUAAACCUUCACAGAACACAGAAACAUUAGAAUUACUACUGAAGGAAUUUUUUGAGUAUUUUGGCAAUUUUGCUUUCGAUAAAAAUUCCAUAAAUAUUCGACAGGGAAGGGAGCAAAACAAACCUGAUUCUUCUCCUCUGUACAUUCAGAAUCCAUUUGAAACUUCUCUCAACAUAAGCAAAAAUGUAAGUCAAAGCCAGCUGCAAAAAUUUGUAGAUUUGGCCCGAGAAAGUGCCUGGAUUUUACAACAGGAAGAUACAGAUCGACCUUCCAUAUCAAGUAAUCGGCCCUGGGGGCUGGUAUCCCUAUUGCUACCAUCUGCUCCAAACAGAAAGUCCUUUACCAAGAAGAAAAGCAAUAAGUUUGCAAUUGAAACAGUCAAAAACUUGCUAGAAUCUUUAAAAGGUAACAGAACAGAAAAUUUCACAAAAACCAGUGGGAAGAGAACAAUUAGUACUCAGACAUGAUGGCUGCUACAUUGUGUAAAGAACUGGGCUUAGCCUAUCAAAUGGUCUGUGGACUUACUUGGAAAAACUGAUUUGAAACUUUCACAGAUCUCAGCUUUCAUCUGAUGUCACUUUUCAUGAUCUUCUCAUUGGCCCCCUUAACCUGGUCUGAAGUUCUGGGAUGUUUUCAGUUUGAUCAGUCUGAUACUCAGUGGCACUUUAUUAAAACAUCAGCUGUGGAGUGUGGCGGUGCACACCUGUAGUCCCAGCUGCUCAGGAGGCUGAGGCAGGAGGAUCUCUUGAGCCCAGGAUUUUGAAUCCAUCGUGGACAACAUAGCAAGAUUCCAUCUCUAAAAAAAAUGAAAAUAAACAUAAGCCACAAGGAAUGGGUGAAAGAUUAUUGUAAUGUGCUUUAACUAAAUAGGUAAAUAUACUAAACAAAUGCUAAAACUCAGUUUUAGGAUGAAACCAUUGUUGAUAUCCACAUCAGUCCCUGUUUAGAAAACAUUUAAAAUGACUUUUAGUUAUGUACAGUACGUUGGCAAUGAAUACAUUAAGCUUCAAAAUUUGGUAGUGCUCUCGAAUAUGUAUAUUUGUAUUUUUCAAGCGAAGUUCUCUUAUUCACAUAUAAAUUAAAGUGGGUUGGUACUGAUAUCAAAAAAUGUUUAUGUUUUUAGAACAGACAUUUCAGUCACUGCAUUCUUAGGUAUUCCAAACCAAAUAUGAUGACAUCAAUAGAUUGCAUUUUAAAAAUAUUGUUUGAUUUUUCUAUUUUCAAAAAUAAAAUUCUGUUUCUAACUAAAAUGUGAUAUUCCCAGUAUUCCUUCACAUCUCUUUUGAGAACUCCCCUCUUCCUGCAGGAAAGAGACAUAUUUGUCUCUCAGUAUAUGCAGAAAAUUGGUUCCAGGACCAUCCACGUACACCCAGAUCUGCACACACUGAACUCCUUCAGUCCUGUGGAGCCCGUGCAUGGGAGAAUUCCACCUUGCACAUAAGCAGAUUUUGCAUCCUGUGAAAGUACUGUAUUUUCUUUCUUUCUUUUUUUUUUUUUUUUUUUUUUGAGACAGAGUCUCGCUCUGUCGCCCAGGCUAGAGUGCAGUGGCGCAAUCUCGGCUCACUGCAAGCUCUGCCUCCCAGGUUCACGCCAUUCUCCUGCCUCAGCCUCUCUGAGUAGCUGGGACUAUAGGUGCCCGCCACCACGCCCGGACAAUUUUUUUGUAUUUUUAGUAGAGACAGGGUUUCACCAUGGUCUCGAUCUCCCGACCUCGUGAUCAGCCCACCUCAACCUCCCAAAGUGCUGGGAUUACAAGCGUGAGCCACCAUGCCUGGCCGAGAAUACUGUAUUUUCAAUCCAAGUUUGGUUGGAAAAAAUCUGUGUGUAAAUGGACUUCGCAGUUGAAACCCAUGUUGUUCAAUGGGCAACUGUAUAUUGAAAUUUAAUUUCCAUUACAUUCUCUGUGGAGCAACUUUUUUGCUUUGUUUCGUUUUGUUUCUGAGACGGAGUUUUGCUCUUGUUGCCCAGGCUGGGGUGCAAUGGCACAAUCUCAGCUCACUGCAACCUCCGCCUCCCGGAUUCAAGUGAUUCUCCUGCCUCAGCUGGGAUUACAGGCGCCCACCACCAAGCCCAGCUAAUUUUUGUAGUUUUAGUAGGGACAGGGUUUCACCAUGUUGGCCAGGCUGAUCUCGAACUCCUGACCUCAGGUGAUCGCCCACCUUGGCCUUCCAAAGUGUUGGAAUUACAGGCGUGAGCCACUGCACCUGGCUUCUGUGGAGUAACUUUCUAUUUAAGAAGCAAGUAAGGCCUGGGCAUAGCGGCACAUGCCUGUAGUCCCAGGUACUUGGGAGGCCGAGGCACAAGGACUGCUUGAACCUGGGAGGCAGAGGCUGCAGUGAGCUGAGAUCACAGCACUGUACUCCAUCCUGGGCGACAGUGAGACUCUCUCAAAGGAAAAGAAGCAAGUAGUAUAGUGUUUAAAAACAGACUUGAGCGAGACUGGCUCAAUGACAAGUUACUCAGUCUCUUGGGGCCCCUGUUUGAUCUGUAAAAUGGGGAUCAUGAUCAGAUCAAUGUGAGGAUUAAGCGAGGGAUGUAGGAAAAUGCUAGGUCAGUGCAUUUUCCUGGCGCGAAGUAAAUGUUACUUCUCUUUAACUGUUGCCUUUCGGUGUUUGUGGUAUGUAAUUACCUUUUUUGCUACUCAAAAUUCAGAUUUAGAGUUUGUAGUACUUUAAAAAUUUUUCCCAUUUAAAUUUUAUGUCAGAAAUUAUAAUGGGUUCUGCAUGGGAUAUUUUAAGAAACUCAGCAUUGUUAUGAAGCAAAUGAAUUCUGUGUCCUUGUGUCUGUGCUAUUGGAUUGCACAUUUGACACCAACAAAUAUCAGUGUUCUGUACAGGCGAUGUCUUUAAAAGCCAUUUUUCAUUUGUUCUUUAUUUUGUUGGGCUAGAAAUCCAUAUUGAUUUAAAAAGCUUAAAAAGCAUAAACCACUUAAGGGUUUCUAAAUGAAAUUUUUUUUUCUGUUCACAGAUAUUUAGUCAGAUAUUUUCUUUUUUAGGUUGGUGCUAGGUGUAAUAUGGUUAUUUAAGCACAUAAAGUAUGUGUAUGGGUUAGCAUUUUCUUUUCUUUUUGGUAAUUUGUAGGACAGCCUUGACACUAGGCUGUUUUACUUUUCAGAAUCAGAUUUAAUUAUGUGAUUAAUUUUAAAUCUACAAAGACUUGUUUUUUGUUUUUUUUUUUGAGAGCAAAUCUUGCUCUGUCACCCAGGCUAGACUGCAGUGGUGCGAUCUCGGCUCACUGCAACCUCUGCCUCCUGGGUUCAAGCGAUACUCCUGCCCCAGCCUCCCAAGUAACUGGGAUUACAGGCGCCUGCCACCAUGCCUAGCUAAUUUUUGUAUGUUAGUAGAGACGGGGUUUCACCAUGUUGGCCAGGCUGGUCUUGAAUUCCUGACCUCAAGUGAUCUACCUGUCUCAGCCUCUCAAAGUGCUGGGAUUACAGGUUACAGGUGUGAGCCACCGCACCUGGCCUACAAAGACCCUUUUUUUUUUUUUUUUUUGAGAUGGGUCUCCCUCUGUCACCCAGGCUGGAGAGUGCAGUGAUCUUGGCUCACUGAAACCUCCACUUCCCGGGUUCAGGUGAUUCUUCUGCCUCAGCCUCCUGAGUAGCUGGGAUUACAGGUGCAUGCCACCACACCUGGCUAAGUUUUCUAUUUUUAGUAGAGAUGGGGUUUUACUCUGUUGGCCAGGCUGGUCUCGAACUCCUGACCUCAGGUGACCUGCCCACCUCGCCCUCCCAAAAUGCUGGGAUUACAGGCAUGAGCCACCACGCCUGGCUGCAAAGACCUUUUAAUACACAGUUUUAAAGUCUGUUCAACUGAAUAUAGACUACAGACAAAUAUAUUUUCUCAUAACUUUAGUGUAUCACAACCCAGAUUUUUAAAAUAUUUUUAUUACGUGAUAGUGAUAACUAGCAAUUAUUUGUCAUUGCUGUUUCUUAAUUAAAAAUAAUUGCAAUGUUAAGUAAAACUUUUUUCAAGUUUUUUUCUUCUAUAACUAUUACUAGGCUUUCAUUCAGUAGCUUUCACCUGUAAUGAGUUUUACUAAGUAUGUGAAAGUAAUUUUGAUAGGAGACUACCCAGAUCAAAACGAUUUCAGCUAUAGCCCACUAGUAUAAUUCCUGGAGCUAUUAUCCAUCUUUAGAAAAUUUGAGAAUUAGCCAGAGACUUUCUAGGAAAUAACGAUUAGCCUGAAACGUUAUAGGAAAACUGUGUGUAAUUAUCUCAUUCACCUUCAGUUACCAUAAAGGAGAAGGGAAAAUAAAGUUGAGUUGAAAUAAGA